AGUCGGCUGGCCAUGGCGGCGCCUUGGAGGCGAUGGCCCACGGGGCUGCUAGCCGUGCUGCGGCCCCUGCUCACCUGCCGGCCCCUGCAAGGCACGACGCUGCAACGGGAUGUGCUGCUCUUUGAGCAUGAUCGGGGCCGCUUCUUCACCAUCCUCGGGCUGUUCUGCGCGGGCCAGGGCGUCUUCUGGGCUUCCAUGGCUGUGGCAGCCGUGUCCCGGCCCCCGGUUCCGGUGCAGCCUCUGGAUGCGGAGGUCCCAAAUCGUGGCCCCUUCGACCUGCGCUCCGCGCUCUGGCGCUACGGUCUGGCCGUCGGCUGCGGCGCCAUCGGGUAUAGCACAAUAAGAAACCGACAAAAACAGCAGCUGAUGACUCACUCCAACAACGCACAGCACCAGAAGGCAAGGAAAUCAAACCUCAGAGGCUAAAUGUUCCAUGACUUCUCCAAGAUCAUGAAGAGCCGCCAGCUGUAUGGGGAACAAGGCCUGGAUCCCACCCCAAAGACAUGGAUUGGAGACCCACCCCUUGGUGACCCUAGACCCGCCAAUAGAUCGUUGUGAAGCUGCAGUUUCCCUAUCUGUAAAAUGGGAGCAUUUAGUCCACCAGCGCGAAAGGCACGGAGGGAGUUUCCCUAUUAUAUGACCGUACACGAAAUCUAGACUGUGACCAAAGUCUCCCGCUCCUCAGCCUCCUCUCCUCCGCAUCCUCAGCCACUAGUCACGCUGGAGAGGAGGCGUGGGAACUGACCUCCGCGGGCCGGGCCUCGGCAACGCGCAUCCUCCCACCCGGCCUAGCCCAGCCCAGAUCGGGGAGGGGGUGCGCGGGGGGAGGAGGUCAGGGGUCACUGAACUUGGGUCACGUGGUCAGCCAAGGGGGCGGGCCCUCGCGGUGCGGGCUCCAAGACUGGUGAGUAAGCAGUCGGCGUCGGGAAUGGGGAGUCCUUGGACCAGAGCAAGGCCUGCUCACCUGAAGACCCCGGCGUGGCGAAGGCUGCUACCGAGACGACGGCGGCGGGGGCGGUGGCGGCGGCGCCCACUCACGAGCUCACACUCAUUCCCUCUCCCGGGGCCCCGGCCCCGCCCUCCCCAAUACAGCCAGUCGGCGGGCGCCUUGGAAAGUUUCCGGCCCUCCAGGAGGCUUCCUGGCUCUUGAUUGGCCAGUGUGAACAGACUGUAGAGACCGGCGGUCACGUGACGCUGAAGAUUCCCGCUUCUUAAAGCAACCUCUCUUGCUACGUUUGCGAGUAGGUGUGUAUUGUUUUAACACACGUUUAAUAAGCAUAUUUUAUUUUUUUUACCACCACAAUAGUAACGAGGAAAUAAACAGUCUCAAAGACA